GCACUUCCUCUCCAGGAAUCCGCGGAGGGAGCGCAGGCUCGAAGAGCUCCUGGACGCAGAGGCCCUGCCCUUGCCAGACGGCGCAGACAUGUCAGAACAAAGUAAGGAUCUGAGCGACCCUAACUUUGCAGCCGAGGCCCCCAACUCCGAGGUGCACAGCAGCCCUGGGGUUUCGGAGGGGGUUCCUCCGUCCGCGACCCUGGCAGAGCCGCAGAGCCCUCCUCUAGGCCCGACGGCCGCUCCGCAGGCCGCGCCGCCUCCCCAGGCCCCGAACGACGAGGGCGACCCGAAGGCCCUGCAGCAGGCUGCGGAGGAGGGCCGCGCCCACCAGGCCCCGAGCGCGGCCCAGCCGGGCCCGGCACCGCCAGCCCCGGCGCAGCUGGUGCAGAAGGCGCACGAGCUCAUGUGGUACGUGCUGGUCAAGGACCAGAAGAAGAUGAUCAUCUGGUUUCCAGACAUGGUGAAAGAUGUCAUCGGCAGCUACAAGAAGUGGUGCAGGAGCAUCCUCCGGCGCACCAGCCUCAUCCUCGCCCGGGUGUUCGGGCUGCACCUGAGGCUAACCAGCCUGCACACCAUGGAGUUUGCGCUGGUCAAAGCGCUGGAGCCCGAGGAGCUGGACAGGGUGGCGCUGAGCAACCGCAUGCCCAUGACAGGCCUCCUGCUCAUGAUCCUGAGCCUCAUCUACGUGAAGGGCCGCGGCGCCAGAGAGAGCGCCGUCUGGAACGUGCUGCGCAUCCUGGGGCUGCGGCCCUGGAAGAAGCACUCCACCUUCGGGGACGUGCGGAAGCUCAUCACUGAGGAGUUCGUCCAAAUGAAUUACCUGAAGUACCAGCGCGUCCCAUACGUGGAGCCGCCCGAAUACGAGUUCUUUUGGGGCUCCCGGGCCAGCCGCGAAAUCACCAAGAUGCAAAUCAUGGAGUUCCUGGCCAGGGUCUUUAAGAAAGACCCCCAGGCCUGGCCCUCCCGAUACAGAGAAGCUCUGGAGGAGGCCAGAGCUCUGCGGGAGGCUAAUCCCACUGCCCACUACCCUCGCAGCAGUGUCUCUGAGGACUAGCAAAGUCUGGAGGCAGAUGAAUGGUUUCUGACCCUCACCAGGGCUGUGGAAGGGUGGGGGUGGGUCAUUAUAGUAUUCAGGAUUUACAGUGCAGUAUUCACGUGUAACUUUUAAGUUUUCAGUACAGUGCUUUUAUACCUUUAAUGCAAUGUUGUAUUCAUUUGGGUACUAUUGUGUAGUAUUUAGGAUGUAUGCAUGUUUGUUUAUAUGUAAGCUUGGUUGGUGCUUUCGCUUUUGUGCUACCUUUCUUGGAUUUUUGUACCAGAGAUGUGCUAAACUGAUGAAAUACAUUGAGAAAGUUUCCAUCUUAUUCUUUUAUAUGGGACUGAUGAUGUGUGUUGGGGUAGACUGCUCCUGCAGAGUUUGGAAGAAGUCACCAGCAAAGCCGGCCUAACCAAGAAAAGUCAAGGCCCUUCAUGACCUUGCUGGGCACAGAAAACACCCUCGUGGAGUACACUAAUUUGAACUGGACUGGUCUCAGUGUGAGCACUUGGCACACUUUACUAAACACAUAUACAACCCCACCGUGAGUCAACUUUAAAGUAAACAUUAAAGAUUCUUGUGAUACAAUCAUUUUUGGAAAAGUGUACUUUAUCAUUUUAACAAAGCAGUAUGGUUGGGAAUGAGACAAUUCUCUAUUUUACAGUGUAUACAGAUACAACUAUUUCCCCUAAUAGGGUGGGAAAAAUCGCUACUCAUGAUUACUCCUAAAUUUGUGAAGUUUAUAGUUCUAUUGUCUUUAAAUGUAACUCAUGUUUAUUUCAAAAACAUUCACAAAUAUAGAAAAGUAUACAAAACAAAACAGUAAGAUUGUCUGUAAUCACAUCAUAUGGGAAUAAAAAACAAAAAUAA